AAGGGCUCCGUGCAUCAGAGGCCCUCAGGAUCACUCCCAGAGGGCUUCCUCAGGGGGAAAGGGAAUCGGCAGGGGAGGGAUGGGGCAAGUUGGGCUGGACGGCAUGUGAGCCAGGGCAGUCAAGUGGGAAGAGGCAAGAGAUGAGACCAGCAGAAAUUGAGGCUAGGUGUGGGGUGAGGGAGGGCAGAGCCCCAGCGGUCUCCCAGCCAGCCUGGGUGGUGAGCAGAGAGCCACUGACUCCCUUCCCUCAUGUCGGAGCUACAGAGGCUGCCUCAUAGCAGGAGGUCUGCCAGGACUUCCAGGUUUCCUGGCCCAGGGAGGCAGAGGAGGUGGGUUUGCUGUCCAGUGCCCUGGGGCCCUUUUCCUAACAGGCCCAGCUCCCCGAUGGCUGCCCUGAGCCAGCUCUCCCUUGUUCACCUGGAGGAGACUAGGUAUGAAGCACAAGGCGGAGCCCUCAGGGGCCUCAGAGAAUUUUCAGGCCACUUAAGACAGAUCCUGGCAGGGCGCGGUGGCUCAUGCCUGUAAUCCCAGCACUUUGGGAGGCCGAGGCAGGCCGAUCACGAGGUCAGGAGAUUGAGACCCUCCUGGCUAACACAGGGAAACCCCAUAUCCACUAAAAAUACAAAACAAAAAAUUAGCUGGGCGCAGUGGCACGCGCCUGUAAUCCUAGCUACUUGGGAGGUUGGGGCAGGAGAAUUGCUUGAACCCGGGAGGUGGAGGUUGCAGUGAGCCCAGAUCGUGCCACUUGCACUCCAGCCUGGGUGACAGAGGGAGACUCCGUCUAAAAAGACAGAUCCUGAGCUGCCUCCCCUGCAGGGCCCUGGAGGAAGGUUGGGUACCGCCCUUGAAGUUUCUUGGUGUGGUGGUCCCCUAGGGUGGACCUGGGCCCUGAGUCAUCCAGUCCUUUGGGGCUGACCAGGCAGUUCCAGCUCCAGGUGAAGGGACUGGGCCAAGGCUGGGGCACCCUCCUCAGCACCUCCUUGGGCCUCCCACAGGGCCACGGGAGUGGGCGAUGGCUGGGUGCGUUCCUAUUCUCCCAGUGCUCAGCUGCCGCAUCCUGAGGCUGCACCACAGCUUUGCUCAUGGACCGAUGCAGGAUGCAGAAUCUACGGCAAAUGACGCCCGGGAGUAUGUGUUACAAAUCACGUGGUGUCCUGCUCCCGGGCCCAGGCUCUUGUGGCGACUCUGUGUGGCUGCUUCCUUGGGCAGAUCUUGGGGAUGUCCACUCUACCCUCUGGGCCUCUGUUCUGGGCCACAGGCAGGCCAGUCGGAGAGCGUGCGGGACGUGCAGUUCAGUAUCCGGGACUACUUCACCUUCGCCUCCACCUUUGAGAACGGCAAUGUGCAGCUCUGGGACAUCCGGCGUCCCGACCGGUGCGAGAGGAUGUUCACAGCCCACAACGGACCCGUCUUCUGCUGCGACUGGCACCCCGAGGACAGGGGCUGGUUGGCCACUGGAGGGCGCGACAAGAUGGUGAAGGUCUGGGACAUGACCACGCACCGUGCCAAGGAGAUGCACUGUGUGCAGACCAUCGCCUCGGUGGCCCGUGUGAAGUGGCGGCCAGAGUGCCGCCACCACCUGGCCACGUGCUCCAUGAUGGUGGACCACAACAUCUAUGUUUGGGACGUGCGCCGGCCCUUCGUGCCAGCUGCCAUGUUUGAGGAACACCGAGACGUCACCACGGGAAUUGCCUGGCGCCACCCCCACGACCCCUCCUUCCUGCUGUCUGGCUCCAAGGACAGCUCGCUGUGCCAGCACCUGUUCCGCGACGCCAGCCAGCCCGUCGAGCGCGCCAACCCUGAGGGCCUCUGCUACGGCCUCUUCGGGGACCUGGCCUUCGCCGCCAAGGAGAGCCUCGUGGCUGCCGAGUCGGGGCGCAAGCCCUACACUGGCGACCGGCGCCACCCCAUCUUCUUUAAGCGCAAGCUGGACCCUGCCGAGCCCUUCGCAGGCCUCGCCUCCAGUGCCCUCAGUGUCUUUGAGACGGAGCCAGGUGGCGGCGGCAUGCGCUGGUUUGUGGACACAGCUGAGCGUUAUGCGCUGGCUGGCCGGCCACUGGCCGAGCUCUGUGACCACAACGCAAAGGUGGCUCGAGAGCUUGGCCGCAACCAGGUGGCGCAAACGUGGACCAUGCUGCGGAUCAUCUACUGCAGCCCUGGCCUAGUGCCCACUGCAAACCUCAACCACAGUGUGGGCAAGGGUGGCUCCUGUGGCCUCCCGCUCAUGAACAGUUUCAACCUGAAGGAUAUGGCCCCAGGGUUGGGCAGUGAGACGCGGCUGGACCGCAGCAAAGGAGAUGCACGGAGCGACACAGUUCUGCUCGACUCCUCGGCCACACUCAUCACCAAUGAGGAUAACGAGGAAACCGAGGGCAGCGACGUACCUGCCGACUACCUGCUGGGUGACGUGGAAGGUGAGGAGGACGAGCUGUACCUGCUGGAUCCGGAACACGCGCACCCCGAGGACCCUGAGUGCGUGCUGCCGCAGGAGGCCUUUCCGCUGCGCCACGAGAUCGUGGACACGCCUCCCGGGCCCGAGCACCUGCAGGACAAGGCCGACUCCCCGCACGUGAGCGGCAGCGAGGCGGAUGUGGCCUCCCUGGCCCCCGUGGACUCCUCCUUCUCGCUCCUGUCUGUCUCACACGCGCUCUACGACAGCCGCCUGCCGCCCGACUUCUUCGGCGUGCUGGUGCGCGACAUGCUGCACUUCUACGCUGAGCAGGGCGACGUGCAGAUGGCUGUGUCUGUGCUCAUCGUCCUGGGUGAACGGGUGCGCAAGGACAUCGACGAGCAGACCCAGGAGCACUGGUACACUUCCUACAUCGACCUGCUGCAGCGCUUCCGCCUCUGGAACGUGUCCAACGAGGUGGUCAAGCUGAGCACCAGCCGCGCCGUCAGCUGCCUCAACCAGGCCUCCACCACCCUGCACGUCAACUGCAGCCACUGCAAGCGGCCCAUGAGCAGCCGGGGCUGGGUCUGCGACAGGUGCCACCGCUGCGCCAGCAUGUGUGCCGUCUGCCACCACGUAGUCAAGGGUCUCUUCGUGUGGUGCCAGGGCUGCAGCCACGGCGGCCACCUGCAGCACAUCAUGAAGUGGCUGGAAGGCAGCUCCCACUGUCCCGCAGGCUGCGGCCACCUCUGCGAGUACUCCUGACGGGGCAUCUGCUGGGCUUGCCCGGGCGGCCGCGUGCAGAACCCCGCCUGGUCUUGUGCCCGAGACGGGCGGAGGCUGGAACUUGAGACCUCAAUAAAGGAAGUAGAGCCGC